GCUCCCAGAGUGCUGAGAUUACAGGCAUGAGCCACUGCACCCGACCUAUGGACUGUUCUCCAUACUUCUCUGUGACAAAAGUAUAUAUUGCAAUUUAAAACAUUUCUGUGAUCAUUAGGCUAUGUUAACAUCCAGAAGAAUGUUUUAUGUCAUUGUAAUUAUCAGUACAGAAUUGAUCACAGAAACAUAAAUAUCAUUGAUCUUGAUAAACAAUUACUAAAUGCACAAAAUACACCGGAAGGAGGUCUCAAAGAGCUGGGGGGUGGGGCCCGUUUAAGGUGCCUUAAUUAAAGGGAUAAUUGAACUGUCCCUGGUACCGGGUACAUCUCUGUUGCUGGAACGUUCCCUGGGAAGAGUGCCUUCCUCUUGUCUAGGCGGGGCAGGCAGGCUGGAGGUGGGGGCUCCCUGGGCACCGGGACUUUCUCCACAGCAGCUUCUCAGGCAGUCCAGUUUUAGGCAGGCGUUUGUGGGGACCUUGCGGCUCUCUGAGUUCCCCACACCGGAGGCCCCUCAGGAUGCUCCUGUGUUUGCACGGGGCGCUUGCUGUGCUGUGUUCGCACACUUGGUCCACGGGUAAGGUCCACGCCACUUCGUCGAGUCACGGGGUCCGUGCUGCUCCAUGUUAAGCUUUACUAUUUAAUUGCCUGUUUUCUAAAUGCGCAGUGUUAAAGGGCAGAAGAUGAACCAUUUCACGAGUAAGCACGCUGCGGCAUUUUCAUCUGGUUGGGCUAAAAUGUAAGACAGUGGAAUUGUGCCUCGGGUUAAAUUUUAAUUUGACAGAAAGGUGUGUUAGAAGCAGAGAAGACUGACAUGGCCAGACUUUAGAUUUGCUAGAGGUUUUUGCCUGGCAGGAAUCUGGUCACCCUGCUCCGCCCUUCUUCCUGCACAGGGCAUCGCUGUGCCUGUUCCGGAGCGAGGCAGCUGGUCUCAGGCCAUCAGGUUGCCAUUAGGAUCAGGGCCAUGGGGUGGGUUGGGAAGGUGGGCCUCUGCCCGAGAACCAGAUGAGGCUGGUCCGGGGCGUUGACACUUGGCAUCCCUGAGAAUUUGCUCAAAUCUGGAGAUGCUCAAAAAGUAGAAAGAUUUACUAUUUUUAGCCUUUAGACCUAAUGAAAUUUGGUAAGAAAAUCAGUUUAGUAACCAAAAAACCACCACUUCCCAUCCCACUCAGAAACAGCACGCUGAGGACUGAGAGCAGUAGAACUUUGCGUUGUGUGAUGGUUUUAUGACAUAAGAGGAGAUUUGACGGACCUGGGGUCUCUGGUGUCUCCCAGCUUUGUUGGAGGAAAGCAGGCUACUCGCCCAACUCUGUGGAAUCGGUAAUGUGGGUCCGGCUGAAGUUUUAACCUGUCUUCUGUCCUCAGGGCUGGCCAUUAGGAGUCCACUAAGAAUGCGUCACUUCCAAUUCGGCCAUGCAGCUAUUUGGGGAGGCGAUGAUGUCGUCAGAUCAUGGGGCCAGUGCCUUCAUUCCAGGGAUGGGUGAGGAGAAGAGCAGUUCCACGGUCGUGUUCUAGGAAUCCUGCGGUUUAAACAGUGAAGAACGGGACCAGGAAGACAGGCCAGCCCCUAAUUACCCCCACAGAACCGGAUUAAAUCACCCUGGAAAGGGGAUCCUCCAUUGGUCCCUUCUCCAAAGCAGCAAAUCCUUAUAUUUUCGUGGUAUUUUGGGUAUUAAUACUGAAAUCAAUGUUUCAGUCUCUUAAAAGACUUUGAGAAACGUUUUGGCUGCUGAAGAAGAACAGGUACAGCAGAGUCCAGCUGGUUCUAGAAAUUCCUGCCCUAACCUGAGGCUUUACUUCAGUAUGCAAAUCCGCUCCCAGCCAGGAGUACUAGAAUAACUGCUAGUGGUUUUUUUCGUGUUGCUUACGUAAAACGGCAUUAAAAGCUUGGAGUGUGGAAGUCCUCCCCCAUCAGGGCCUGCGCACCACCACCCUCUGCUGGAUGAAGCCGGAUCCCGGGGCUGCGGCCACGGCCGCUCUGCUGUCCCUAACCGUGCCCAUUUGAAGGGCAGCUCUGAUUUGGUGGCGAGAACGACACCCACAGCUCAGGUGGUCUUGUUAUGGACUUGCAGCCUGGAGCUGGUGUCUCUAGUGUGACAGGUGUCUCCCUAGAUCAUCCAGUCACUCGAUGGGGAUUACCAGCGGACCACCUGUUUGUAUCACCUUCCCACCUCUCUGUAGCAAGAAAAAUCACUUCAGCACCUCUUCAGUAAUAAUGAUGAAACUGGUAUUAACUGAAUGGCAAUUAUGGAUUUUUAACUCUAAUUCACAGUAAACCAGCAAGCCAUAUGUUUAAAAUCCAACCAAAAAUCGUUCUGUGUUGCUGCAUGUCUCAUACCGUUGUGAGAAGUUGUGAGAUAGCCACUUGUGCAAAGAGGAAUGUAAGUGUUACCUGCCCGAGGAACACAGCAGAAGCAGAAAGAGAAGACGUCUUAAUUUAUCAUUACAGAUAUAUGAAAGCAUUAUUUAUAUAGAUAGAAUAUAUAGAUAAAUACAUAUAUUUUUGGUGGUAAUGAAAAUGGCUCCGCAGAAUGCCGACCCGGAAUCUAUGCAAGUUCAAGAGUUAUCCGUGCCCCUGCCGGACCCGCAGAAAGCCGGAGGCGCAGAGGCCGAGAACUGCGAGACCAUCAGCGAGGGGUCCAUAGACCGAAUCCCCAUGCGCCUGUGGGUGAUGCACGGGGCGGUGAUGUUUGGCAGGGAGUUCUGUUACGCCAUGGAAACCGCUCUGGUCACACCAAUACUGUUGCAGAUUGGCCUUCCGGAGCAGUACUACAGCCUCACCUGGUUCCUGAGCCCCAUCCUUGGCCUCAUCUUCACACCUCUCAUUGGGUCUGCGAGUGACCGGUGCACCCUGAGCUGGGGCCGCCGGCGGCCCUUCAUCCUCGCCCUCUGCGUUGGCGUCCUCUUUGGCGUUGCACUUUUCCUUAACGGCUCUGCCAUCGGUCUGGCCCUCGGCGAUGUCCCCAACCGGCAGCCCAUUGGCAUCGUGCUCACGGUGCUGGGAGUGGUGGUCCUGGACUUCAGCGCCGAUGCCACCGAGGGGCCCAUCCGUGCCUAUCUGCUGGACGUGGUGGACAGCGAGGAGCAGGACAUGGCCCUCAACAUCCACGCCUUCUCUGCCGGCCUCGGCGGAGCCAUCGGCUACGUGCUGGGUGGGCUGGACUGGACCCAGACCUUCCUGGGCAGCUGGUUCCGGACCCAGAACCAGGUGCUCUUCUUCUUUGCCGCCAUCAUCUUCACGGUGUCCGUGGCCCUGCACCUGUUCAGCAUCGACGAGGAGCAGUACAGCCCGCAGCAGGAGCGCAGCGCUGAGGAGCCCGGCGCCCUGGAUGGGGGCGAGCCGCACGGCGUCCCUGCCUUCCCAGACGAGGUACAGUCGGAGCACGAGCUGGCCCUGGACUACCCGGACGUGGACAUCAUGCGCAGCAAAAGCGACUCGGCAUUGCACGUGCCGGACACCGCGCUGGACCUGGAGCCCGAGCUGCUGUUCCUGCACGACAUCGAGCCCUCCAUCUUCCACGACGCCUCCUACCCCGCCACCCCCCGCAGCACCAGCCAGGAGCUCGCCAAGACCAAGCUGCCCCGCCUGGCCACCUUCCUCAAGGAAGCCGCCAAGGAGGACGAGACCUUGCUGGAUAAUCACUUGAAUGAAGCUAAAGUCCCAAACGGAAGUGGCUCCCCCACAAAAGACGCCCUCGGCGGCUACACCAGGGUGGACACGAAGCCCUCGGCCACGUCGAGCUCCAUGCGGCGGCGGCGGCACGCGUUCCGCAGGCAGGCCUCCAGCACCUUCUCCUACUACGGCAAGCUUGGGUCCCACUGCUACCGCUACCGGCGCGCCAACGCCGUGGUGCUGAUCAAGCCGUCGCGCAGCAUGAGCGACCUGUACGACAUGCAGAAGCGGCAGCGGCAGCACCGGCACCGGAACCAGAGCGGGGCCACCACCUCCAGCGGGGACACCGAGAGUGAGGAGGGGGAGGGCGAGACCACGGUGCGCCUGCUGUGGCUCUCCAUGCUGAAGAUGCCCAGGGAGCUGAUGCGGCUGUGCCUCUGCCACCUCCUCACCUGGUUCUCUGUCAUCGCCGAGGCCGUGUUCUACACCGACUUCAUGGGCCAGGUCAUCUUCGAAGGCGACCCCAAGGCCCCCUCGAACUCGACCGCCUGGCAAGCCUACAACGCCGGGGUCAAGAUGGGCUGCUGGGGCCUGGUCAUUUAUGCCGCCACUGGUGCUAUUUGUUCAGCCCUGUUACAGAAGUACUUGGACAACUACGACCUGAGCGUCAGGGUGAUCUACGUGCUGGGGACGCUGGGCUUCUCUGUCGGCACAGCCGUGAUGGCCAUGUUUCCCAACGUCUACGUCGCCAUGGUCACCAUCAGCACCAUGGGCAUCGUCUCCAUGAGCAUCUCCUACUGCCCGUACGCCCUGCUGGGCCAGUACCAUGACAUCAAGCAGGCCCAGUCACAUUUCCCUGAGGGGGAAGCUCCAGCCCCGUGUUUUCCACUUGGAUGGGAGGAAAGCCACCCAGUACAUCCACCACAGCCCCGGGAACUCCAAGCGAGGGUUUGGCAUAGAUUGUGCCAUCCUGUCCUGCCAAGUGUACAUCUCGCAGAUCCUGGUGGCCUCUGCCCUUGGGGGCGUGGUCGACGCCGUGGGGACUGUCCGCGUCAUCCCCAUGGUGGCCUCUGUGGGCUCUUUCCUGGGCUUCCUGACGGCCACAUUCCUGGUGAUCUAUCCCAACGUGUCAGAGGAGGCCAAGGAGGAGCAGAAAGGCCUGUCUUCCCCGUUGGCCGGCGAAGGCAGGGCCGGUGGGAACAGCGAAAAGCCCACCGUGCUGAAGCUCACGCGGAAGGAGGGCCUGCAGGGACCGGUGGAGACAGAGUCCGUGACGCCUGCAGGUAUUGACGUCUGUCAGAUCUCGUCACAUUGGCUGGUGCCGCAGCUGUUGGAGAGUAUUUUUCUUUAUGAUUAUUUUAGAAAAAAAAUUUUCUUUUCCACAAUGUGGUUCUCUUAGAAGAAUGACGUAUCUUCUUUUCCUCAGCGAGUUGGACACAUUGUGCCCAGGGCAGCCCUGUCCUUGGGCAGCGACCGCACACCAAAGCUGGGAGGAGGCUGGUCCGGGGGGCCUGGGCAGAAGACAGUGAUUUGCAGGGGUGGCUCCCAGACACCCUGCCCAGGGAUGGGCUGGGCACCACCUGGGGGCGGAGCGUGAGCUCCAGACGAGCUCCUGCGUGCGCGUGUGAGUGUGUCUGCGCCCAGCCAUGUGACCCCGCUCGUCCCGUCUGAAGGACUCUCCUAGGAGGCCAGGUUGCCCCUCCAGACCGCUCCCAACGUCAGGGGGAAGGAAACGUUGACUUUCACUGCACUUUGAUUCGUCUCUAAACCAUUUGCUGGGGAUUCCUGAGAGCAGAGCUCCCAGCGGGCCCUGCCUCCCAAGUCCCGCCGCAAGGCUACCUCGGGUGUGUGGAUGUGCGAGGGCCUCCCCCGCUUGCGAAGGGGACAUGCGUGCUGGAACCUGUCGGAACUCCAUGCCUUCCUCGCCUGCUCACCUGCUCGACGCUGGAAUCGGGACAGGUGCAAAGGGACGCAGACGUCUGGGACAGCUAAGGCCCGUGUCACCGGAGGGCUCCGCACAGUCGUUCUGGUUUCAACGAAUAAGCAAAACUCGGGCAAGUACUGCAGCUAUUUGGAAAUGUUUUCCAAACCACAGUCUCUUUAGAACUAAGCCUAUUUGAAACGGUCGGUGUAGGCUUACUGAGAUCAGGAGACAGGGAGGCCCCGCACAUCACACAGAUAAAGUCAGACAAUUGUAAUUAAUACUUUUGCUGCCUCAAGUUGUUUUUUAAAUAAAGUACUUUGAAAUGCAUGAGAAUCAUGCUGCAAUAUGAUCAUUCUAGAGCAAAUAUAUAUAUACACGUAUAUAUAUUUCAAGAUGAAACUAAAGCAGUUUUUAAAUAAAUUACUUGAAUUUUCUGUGUAUUUAAAGGAACGACUGUUUAAUGUACUUGAUGGGCCUCUGGUCUUGCCGUGUCUCCUGCCGCUGGUGGCACUUUGUAGAUUGUGUGUUUGUGUCCGGGUGGCAGUUGGGUACCUGCUCACGCACGGUGUGUCUGCCAGGCCACGGUGUCCCAGGAUCGCAGAGGGCUGACUUUCAAGACUUCAAGAACAUUUUCUGGAUGUGUGGAAACUUGAGAAUGGCCUUGUGAAUCUCGUGCUUGGACAGGGCAAGUCCGACUACUGAAAGUGCUGCCAGCUUUGCUGCGAGCCCUCCGGCCAGCGGGAGCCCCGUGGGCUGGGCACUGUGGCCCUUCUUCUCUGGGGGACGGCACCCCUGGCUUCCUCACCUCGGCCGGGCGUCCGUGGCAGCUCACUCUAUGCAACUUGAUCCUCUAGCGGCUUUAAGACUGUAGAUCCCCUCUCUGAGACCUGGCUGUACUUGUCAGGAUCUCGAGGCGCAGCUCCCGUCUUAGCUGGUUUCUCCGGCUUCUCGUCCUGACGACUAUAAAACAGUUGGAGGCAAGAAAGCAGCGGAUGUGGGGUGGCAGUGGCCUGACCCGAAUCAAGAUCCGACCCAAACCACACCAAAUGUGGGUUCAUCUGGGGGCCACCCCUUGCCUGAGGCUUCCCACCCUCAUCUGAAGGCCCAGGGGCCGGAUCCAGGGCUCACCAAAGCCGAUUCCUCGCCAGCUGGGAGUGCAGAAGUCUCAGGGCCUGGCUGCGACUUGAUUUUUAGGAGGAAGAGGGGCUUCGCAACCCCCCUCUGAAUAGUGUGUUAACCCUUGAGAUCCCAGCCUCGACUAAUCUGAAGUAAGGACAACAAAGGCCAUUCAGUGCCCUCCACAUGGCCUUGCCACAGUCACUGUCAGGGUAUGAACGUGCCGGAAGCCAGUGCCAGCCAGGGACAGGCGUGACUGUUGUGUGCUCCUCGGUGACAGGAGUCGGUGGCUGCACACUUUGUAGACUCGUCAAGCUGUCAGCACUUCAGGUGUUUGCAAGCAAAGCCCUUCUUAGUGUGCAGGUCAGUGUGCAGAGCCCAAAUGAGGGGACCGCAGGGGCUGGGGUCCAGGGUCAGUAGAGUCGGUUUCUGGAGCUGCCUUCCUGGGAGGCAGGUGUGGGUGACCGGGGCUCUGGCGGUGCGUGUGGGCCCGGCCUGGCCACAGCGGGGACCAGGUCACGACAUCUUUGGCCUCAACCCCUCCCCUGCACUGAGAUUAUUUCCAGAUUGCACUCACUUGAAACCGUCCGUGUCGUCACCUUGUGUCUUAAGGGAAGCCGAGAAGAAGGGCAGACGGGCAGGCUGUCUUGUCUGCAAAGCGCCAUUGCGCCCGCAGCUUGUGUGGGUCAGGCUGCAGCUCGGGUGUCUGUGGCUUCUAACCUUGUACCUCAGACGGAUGCAGUAACAAGGCGGGGCUGGGGACGCCGGUCAGUGUCAAAGGGGAGGUGCUCUGGCUGAUAGCCUUGCCCGAGAGGGACGAGGAGGCCGUGCGGGUGCCCCCUGGGGAAGCUGGCCAGCCAUCCAGUGCUGAGGACGCAGCUGGAGUUGGGCUCGUGGCACCCUUGGGGUGUGGGCUGUGCAGGCUGGUGGCCUGGGUGCCUCUGCACACUGAGUGGAGUGUCAGGCAGGGUGUGUCGGUUGGUCGAGUCUUGUGUAAUGUGCGCAGACCAGUUACCAAACUAGGAUAAUGUUGGUCUCAUUUGUGGUGGUUUUGUUCCCUAUACAAGUCAGCUAAGUAAAGACUCUUUUAACGAGCUUCCCCUUAACACAUGGCAGAAGUUUCCAGGUGCAGGAAUGCGAGCUGGCGGGAAGGGGCAGAGGCCGUGAGCUCUCAGCUGGGCCGGCCUGCCUGUGUCCCCUUUCCUGGGUCUGUCGGCAGACUGGCAUCAUGACGUUCCCUGGUGGCUGAAGAGCUAGCUUUGGAGUGUUGUUUUUCUCACUCUCAGGCAGGGGCCUUAGCUGGAAUCCUCCAACCUGCCACUGAACACGUCAGUGCUGUGUGCUGCCUCUUGGACACCUGCCCUUGAAAGCCUCAGGCCCCUGGGAGAAGCACUCUGUCCAGUCCUGUCCCCGGGGGGGAGGCAGGGCCACUGAGCCCUCCUCAGAUGGUUAGUGGCUUCCAACAGCCAUCAGGAGUGUUUCUUGAAUGCCCCAGGUGUGGAGGACUUGGUCUGUGACCACCUAGAACCCCAGAGCUGAACAGGAAGCCGUCCCUGCAGCAACAAGAGGGCUGGAAGGGGGAGCUGCAGGCCACCCUCGGCUCUCCCACUGCUGGGGCGGUGAUGUUCGGGUGACAUGUUUGAAAAAUACUCUUAAAGAUACCAACUGUUCCCUUAUAUGGCUAAUGGUUUGUGCAGCCACCAGCGAUGGCGGCCCCUAUUAGAGACCAGGUUUGUUAAAACACCAAAUAUUGCUGUCCACACUAGACAUUAACCGGCUUCAGAAAAGAUGGACACCUUUUCCCACGCUGUUUCGCUUCUUAACUUUGGUCCAGCUUUAGCCACCACACAGCGUGUGAGGGACUGCUGCUGCGGAGUCAGCCUCGUUUGUCCCUCCGCCUCCCACCAGCACGCGCCGCUUCUGAGAGACACCAGCUCCCUGCCUCCAAGCCUGGUGCCACAGGCCUGUCGUGAGGGACCCCUGCUUCCGAGAGCUCCUGGGGGGGUUCUGCCCUUCACCACCUGGGAGAGGUGUCAGUUCAGUUCCGAGUUGAACAAGGCCCGUGCACACAGCAUGUUGGGGGCCCAGCCCAAAGUUCUUGUCACCUCCUCAUGCAAAGCCAGCCAUCACCCUCCGGCCAGAGCUCAAGGUGGCCCCUUGGCCAGCCCCUCCUUGGGUCCUCCAGGAGGACUGAGCACCCCUCCUAGCGGCAUCCCUUGCCCUCCACAGUGCUGCCAGGGGCACGUCGCUCUGUGCCGUGGACUGAGACCAUCCCCUGGUGACAGAAUGACCCGUUUGUUGGAAAUGCCUCGUUGCCAGAGAAACUCCCCAGGCAUCUCGGAACGAAACUAUUUAGUUCCAUUGUGAACUGGCCACGGGACAGCUUUUUAUCAACUUAUUAAGUUGGAGCACUGUAAUCGCGCUUGCUGAGUUAGCAGUGGUGGUAAGCGUGUGUUAAACACAUAAUGUUACGUUUUAGGAGAGAGAGGUCGUAAGGAAGUGUCGUGUCGCUCAUGACUCUCUUCUAUUAGUUGGGUAACAGUGGCCUCAUGUUUGUGUCUGUGUGUACACAGAGCCCUUAGGUUCUGCUCUGUUUCUUUGCCAGGUGAAUGUUUGUGGCAUGCGCUGCUGUCCGCGCCCCUCUGUCCUGCGCAGGGUUCAGCUGUGCGGCGCCCUGAUUUCCUCCAUGCACACAGAACCUCCUUGUGUCUGUUUCUCUGUUCCUCUGUGGCUGACUCAAUAAACUUUUCCCUCUGA